GCGCAGCGUCGCACCUCUGCCCAAUGAGGUGCCCCUGACGUGCCUGCUGCGGCUGCCCUGCUCCCCCCAGCCUCCCUGCAUCCCGGGAUGGGGGAGGGCGCCAGGCGCAGCUCCCGGACCCUCAGGGGUCUCCCCGCCCUACCCCACCAGCCUGGGUUCGGUACCUCGGGGCUCAGAUGUGCAGUCAGCUGUUAAUGUGGCAAAAUUUGGGGAAGUCCUCUGCAGCCGCAAAAUCCAGUUCCCACCAGUUGGAGGCCGGGCGGGGAAGGGUGGGGACAGACAGCACUCCGCUGUGGGAGGCAAGGCCAGGCGGGUGCUGCCUGGGACCCAGUGACUCAGCACCCCUGCCCGGAUCAACUGGACUUUUGCCCCCUGCUCCGCCAGCCUCCUGCUUGGAUCUCUCCUGGGUCUCCCUGCUGCGCCUGUCCAGGAUGCAGGGAGCUCGGGCUCCCAGGGACCAGGGCCGGUCCCCCGGCAGGAUGAGCGCUCUAGGCCGGUCCUCGGUCAUCUUGCUUACCUACGUGCUGGCCGCCACAGAACUUACCUGCCUCUUCAUGCAGUUCUCCAUCGUGCCAUACCUGUCUCGGAAACUGGGCCUGGAUUCCAUUGCCUUCGGCUACCUGCAAACCACCUUCGGGGUGCUGCAGCUGCUGGGCGGGCCGGUAUUUGGCAGGUUCGCAGACCAGCGCGGGGCGCGGGCGGCGCUCACGCUCUCCUUCCUGGCUGCCUUGGCGCUCUACCUGCUCCUGGCGGCCGCCUCCAGCCCGGCCCUGCCCGGGGUCUACCUGCUCUUCGCCUCGCGCCUGCCCGGAGCGCUCAUGCACACGCUGCCAGCCGCCCAGAUGGUCAUCACGGACCUGUCGGCACCCGAGGAGCGGCCCGCGGCCCUGGGCCGGCUGGGCCUCUGCUUCGGCGUCGGAGUCAUCCUCGGCUCCCUGCUGGGCGGGACCCUGGUCUCCGCGUACGGGAUUCAGUGCCCGGCCAUCCUGGCUGCCCUGGCCACCCUCCUGGGAGCUGUCCUCAGCUUCACCUGCAUCCCCGCCAGCACCAAAGGGGCCAAAACUGACGCCCAGGCUCCACUGCCAGGCGGCCCCCGGGCCAGUGUGUUCGACCUGAAGGCCAUCGCCUCCCUGCUGCGGCUGCCAGACGUCCCGAGGAUCUUCCUGGUGAAGGUGGCCUCCAACUGCCCCACAGGGCUCUUCAUGGUCAUGUUCUCCAUCAUCUCCAUGGACUUCUUCCAGCUGGAGGCCGCCCAAGCUGGCUACCUCAUGUCCUUCUUCGGGCUCCUCCAGAUGGCCAAAGUGCCCGCCUUGCAGGGUCCUUGGCAGAUGAGAUGACCUAACGUGGCAAAGUGGUUAGACCAGCGUGGGCCCCUUUGGAGGUCCCAUAGGAGCAAGACGCCAGCCCUCAGAGGCCACGCUGUCAUGGUAGGAUAAGACGCCAGCCCUCAGAGGCCACACUGUCAUGGAAGGAUGCCCUGAAACCCUGGCAGCUCCGAUGCGGCAGGUGUCUGUCUGCCAGCCCCCCAGAACCGCUCAGCUCCCGGGCCGGGGCGAGACACCUCCACCACCAGCUCCUCUGGGCUUCUGGACCAGACCCUGGGUGGUGGGGACAGGUGAUGAUUUGCCACCACCCAGGAUGGCUGCCUGACAGCCAGAGUGCGGGGCGGGGGGGCUAUUCUGGGACCCGCCAGGGUGGGGGUGGGGGCUCUCGGCCUCUCCGGAAGCCUGUGGCAUUCCUGGCACCUCCAAGCCAUCUGCUCUUCAGCCUCUGGGCCCAGGACUAGACUAGUGCUAAAAUAGCUGCUCCUGGGAGGGGCUGGACCCCCACCGUGGGCAGAGAGGGCCUCUGCUUUUUGGGGCAGGAGGGGCCACCCUGGCAGGGUAAAAAGAGAUAAACAGAAAAACAACAGCAACAAUAAUAGUAACAAUCCGGGGUUGUUGCCAUGGGGCCUGUUCUGAACAGGCUGCGCCCAGCUCACUGCGAGGAAGGACGCUUAGCCAGGCCCUGGCUGAAGCCUGCAGCUGGGCUGGACACAGCAGUCAUUGGCCUGUGUUGUGGGGGACUUGGGCCUGCCAUGGCUGCAGUGGGGACCCUGCCUGAGACAGACAGAGCUGGGGUGGUGACCAACACCGUCGGGGCACCCUCGCAGGAACUGGGCCUGGUGAACUGCCCAGGGACGGGGAAGGAGCAGGGUGAGGCAUGGGGACCCCGACACAGGUUGAGCAGCGGGAGAGGAGGCUGAGGAGGGGAAGGAGGGGGCCCGCAGAGUAGCCCCCAGACCCCAAGUCCGGUCAGGGACAAGCUUGUUAGCUCCAGGUUCAUGUCACAACCUGCAGGGCUCCUAAGUUCAAGCUUUUUUAAACUUAAUGGGCAAACUGAGACGCAACACAAAUAGGCUUCUGACCUUGGUGUCUGAGUCCUGGAUCUGAAGUCCUUCACGGCACUCACUGUGAGCCCCUCUUAGACGCACUGCACGAAGUGAGCUUGCCAGCUCUUCCUUUAAGAAACGUGUUAGGCCGGGCGCGGUGGCUCACGCCUGUAAUCCCAGCACUUUGGGAGACCGAGGCGGGCGGAUCCCAAGGUCAGGAGAUUGAGACCAUCCUGGCGAACAUGGUGAAACCCCGUCUCUACCAAAAAUACAAAAAAAAAAAAAAAAAUUAGCCGGGCCUGGUGGCAGGCACCUGUAGUCCCAGCUACUCGGGAGGCUGACGCAGGAGAAUGGCGUGAACCCGGGAGGCGGAGCUUGCAGUGAGCCGAGAUCGCGCCACUGCAGUCCACGCUGGGCGACAGAGCGAGACGCCAUCUCAAAAAAAAAAAAAAAAAAGGUGUUAAAAUCCCAAAAAACCCUAAGAUAAAGCAAGUGUGAAAGUAAGAUUUUUAAACCAUUUAUGGUUCCGGUUGGAAGCAGUUUCUGUUCUGCCUGGCAGGAAUUUGGGAGGGUGACUGGUCCCCUGCAGAGGUGCUGCAGGCUGGGCCUGCCCUGUGGGCAGAUACUGAGCCCAGGGGCUCCUCCAGCCGGGGCCACCCCUGCACUCCCAGGCGCGUUGGCCCAGCACGCCCUGCUUAGUGGAGGAGCUGAGAUGACCAGAUAGAGAGCCUCGCCCUGGCCUGGGAGCAGCCUGCGGCCAAGCCUGUCCCACCGAGCCCAUCCCCGGGAGCAGCCUGCGGCCGAGCCUGUCCCACCGAGCCCAUCCCCGGGAGCAGCCUGCGGCCGAGCCUGUCCCACCGAGCCCAUCCCCGGGAGCAGCCUGCGGCCGAGCCUGUCCCACCGAGCCCAUCCCCGGGAGCAGCCUGCGGCCGAGCCUGUCCCACCGAGCCCAUCCCCGGGAGCAGCCUGCGGCCGAGCCUGUCCCACCGAGCCCAUCC